UUUUCCUUGUUUUAUUUUUGUUUUUUUUUUGUGACAGAGUCUCCCUCUGUUGCCCAGGUUGGAGUGCAGUGGCACGAUCUUAGCUCACUGCAACCUCUGCCUCCCGGGUUUAAUCAAUUCCCACCUUAUAUAGCCUCCUGAGUAGCUGGGAUUACAGGCAUGCACCACCAUGCCCAGCUAAUCUGUUGCAUUUUUAGUGAAGACGGUUUCACCAUAUUGGCCAGGCUGGUCUUGAACUCCCGACCUCAGGUAAUCCACCCACCUCGGCCUCCCAAAGUGCUGGGAUUAUAGAUGUGAGCUACCUCGCCCAGCCAUGGUUUGUAAUUUUUUUUUUUUUUUUUUGAGACAGAGUCUCACUCUGUUGCCCAGGCUGGAGUGCAGUGGCAUGAUCUCAGCUCACUGCAACCUCUGCUUCCCGGGUUCGAGAUUCUCUUACCUCAGCCUCCCAAAUAGCUGGGACUACAGGUGCAUGUCACCACACCUGGCUAAUUUUUGUAUUUUUACUAGAGACUGGGUUUCACCAUGUUGGCCAGGCUGGUCUUGAACUCCUGACCUUGUGAUCCACCUGCCUUGGCCUCCCAAAGUGCUGGGAUUACAGGCGUGAGCCACCGCACCCGGCCCAUGGUUUGUAAUUUUUAGCAUGCAAGUUCUGUAGAUGGUUUGCUAAGUUUAUACCAAAGUAUUUAAUUUUCCUUGGAGUAAUUAUGAAUGUCUUUAACUUUGGUUUUCAUGUUUCUUGUUGGUAUACAUCAAUGCAAGCGAUUGUUGUGUGCUGAUCUUGCAUUCUGCAAUGUUGCUGAGCUCACCUGCUCAACCCAAGAGUUCCGACAUGUAGGGAGGAGGAGCCCCUCAACAAUGCACGCUCAACAGAGACUGAACAAUGGAGGCCUCUCCAUCCUAAACAAACAGAAACCUGUGCCUACUCCUCUGAGAGCCGUGUCCUCCAUUGUAAAAUGCAGCUGUGGCUCAGCUUUGCACCUGUGGCUGACGUCAUUGCUGAGGACUUGGUCCUGUCCAUGGAGCAGAUCAACUGGCUGUCACUGGUCUACCUCGUGGUAUCCACCCCAUUUGGCGUGGCGGCCAUCUGGAUCCUGGACUCCGUCGGGCUCCGUGCGGCGACCAUCCUGGCCAAGCUGGCUGCCUUGUGGUUCCCAGAGCACCAGCGAGCCACGGCCAACAUGCUCGCCACCAUGUCGAACCCUCUGGGCGUCCUUGUGGCCAAUGUGCUGUCCCCUGUGCUGGUCAAGAAGGCUCGGUGUCUAUACCAUCCCUGCUGGCGUCGUCUGCCUGCUGUCCACCAUCUGCCUGUGGGAGAGUGUGCCCCCCACCCCGCCCUCUGCCGGGGCUGCCAGCUCCACCUCAGAGAAGUUCCUGGAUGGGCUCAAGCUGCAGCUCAUGUGGAACAAGGCCUAUGUCAUCCUGGCUGUGUGCUUGGGGGGAAUGAUCGGGAUCUCUGCCAGCUUCUCAGCCCUCCUGGAGCAGAUCCUCUGUGCAAGCGGCCACUCCAGUGGGUUUUCCGGCCUCUGUGGCGCUCUCUUCAUCACGUUUGGGAUCCUGGGGGCACUGGCUCUCGGCCCCUAUGUGGACCGGACCAAGCACUUCACUGAGGCCACCAAGAUUGGCCUGUGCCUGUUCUCUCUGGCCUGCGUGCCCUUUGCCCUGGUGUCCCAGCUGCAGGGACAGACCCUUGCCCUGGCUGCCACCUGCUCGCUGCUCGGGCUGUUUGGCUUCUCGGUGGGCCCCGUGGCCAUGGAGUUGGCGGUCGAGUGUUCCUUCCCCGUGGGGGAGGGGGCUGCCACAGGCAUGAUCUUUGUGCUGGGGCAGGCCGAGGGAAUACUCAUCAUGCUGGCAAUGACGGCACUGACUGUGCGACGCUCGGAGCCGUCCUUGUCCACCUGCCAGCAGGGGGAGGAUCCACUUGACUGGACAGUGUCUCUGCUGCUGAUGGCCGGCCUGUGCACCUUCUUCAGCUGCAUCCUGGCGGUCUUCUUCCACACCCCAUACCGGCGCCUGCAGGCCGAGUCUGGGGAGCCCCCCUCCACCCGUAACGCCGUGGGCGGCGCAGACUCAGGGCCGGGUGUGGACCGAGGGGGAGCAGGAAGGGCUGGGGUCCUGGGGCCCAGCACGGCGACUCCGGAGUGCACGGCGAGGGGGGCCUCGCUAGAGGACCCCAGAGGGCCCGGGAGCCCCCACCCAGCCUGCCACCGAGCGACUCCCCGUGCGCAAGGCCCAGCAGCCACCGACGCGCCCUCCCGCCCCGGCAGACUCGCAGGCAGGGUCCAAGCGUCCAGGUUUAUUGACCCGGCUGGGUCUCACUCCUCCUUCUCCUCCCCGUGGGUGAUCACGUAGCUGAGCGCCUUGUAGUCCAGGUUGCCCGCCACAUCGAUGGAGGCGAACUGGAACAUCUGGUCCACCUGCGGGCGGGGGCGAAAGGGCUCCUUGCGGGCUCCGGGAGCGAAUUACAAGCGCGCACCUGCA